GAAGAUACAACCUGACAGCACAGCCUGAGAUCUUGGGGAUCCCUCAGCCUAACACCCACAGACGUCAGCUGGUGGAUUCCCGCUGCAUCAAGGCCUACCCACUGUCUCCAUGCUGGGCUCUCCCUGCCUUCUGUGGCUCCUGGCCGUGACCUUCUUGGUUCCCAGAGCUCAGCCCUUGGCCCCUCAAGACUUUGAAGAAGAGGAGGCAGAUGAGACUGAGACGGCGUGGCCGCCUUUGCCGGCUGUCCCCUGCGACUACGACCACUGCCGACACCUGCAGGUGCCCUGCAAGGAGCUACAGAGGGUCGGGCCGGCGGCCUGCCUGUGCCCAGGACUCUCCAGCCCCGCCCAGCCGCCCGACCCGCCGCGCAUGGGAGAAGUGCGCAUUGCGGCCGAAGAGGGCCGCGCAGUGGUCCACUGGUGUGCCCCCUUCUCCCCGGUCCUCCACUACUGGCUGCUGCUUUGGGACGGCAGCGAGGCUGCGCAGAAGGGGCCCCCGCUGAACGCUACGGUCCGCAGAGCCGAACUGAAGGGGCUGAAGCCAGGGGGCAUUUAUGUCGUUUGCGUAGUGGCCGCUAACGAGGCCGGGGCAAGCCGCGUGCCCCAGGCUGGAGGAGAGGGCCUCGAGGGGGCCGACAUCCCUGCCUUCGGGCCUUGCAGCCGCCUUGCGGUGCCGCCCAACCCCCGCACUCUGGUCCACGCGGCCGUCGGGGUGGGCACGGCCCUGGCCCUGCUAAGCUGUGCCGCCCUGGUGUGGCACUUCUGCCUGCGCGAUCGCUGGGGCUGCCCGCGCCGAGCCGCCGCCCGAGCCGCAGGGGCGCUCUGAAAGGGGCCUGGGGGCAUCUCGGGCACAGACAGCCCCACCUGGGGCGCUCAGCCUGGCCCCCGGGAAAGAGGAAAACCCGCUGCCUCCAGGGAGGGCUGGACGGCGAGCUGGGAGCCAGCCCCAGGCUCCAGGGCCACGGCGGAGUCAUGGUUCUCAGGACUGAGCGCUUGUUUAGGUCCGGUACUUGGCGCUUUGUUUCCUGGCUGAGGUCUGGGAAGGAAUAGAAAGGGGCCCCCAAUUUUUUUUUAAGCGGCCAGAUAAUAAAUAAUGUAACCUUUGCGGUUUAAGAGGAUAAAAUGGAGGAUAUUAUUAUGUGGGUAUUUAUAUGACCUUUGUAACCAUUUAAAAAUGUAAAAACGACCUGACUUAGUAAUGCGAACCUAUAGUAGCAGCUACUCCAGAGGCUGAAAUGGGAGGAUCUCUUGAGCCCAGGAGUUGGAGUCCAGUCCAGCCAGGGCAACACAGCCAGACGCCCUUGUUUUUUAUUUUGUUUUGUUUUGGUUUUUUGUUUUUUGAGGAGUUUCCCUCUGUCACACAAGCUGGAGGGCAAUGGCGCCAUCUCAGCUCACUGCAACGUCCACCUCCUGGGUUCAAGCGAUUCUCCUGCCUCAGCAUCCUAAUUAGUUGGGAUUACAGGCGCCCACCACCAUGCCCGGCUAAUUUUUGUGUUUUUUUAGUAGAGACGGGGUUUCACCAUGUUGUCAGGCUGGUCUCAAACUCCUGACCUCAGGUACUCCACCCGCCUUGGUCUCUCAAAGUGCUGGGAUUACAGGCAUAAGCCACUGUGCCCAGGCAGACCCCCUUCUUUAAAGAUGUAAAACCCGGCCGGGCGCGGUGGCUCACGCCUGUAAUCCCAGCACUUUGGGAGGCUGAGGCGGGCAGAUCACGAAGUCAGGAGAUCGAGACCAUCCUGGCUAACACGGUGAAACCCCGUCUCUACUAAAAAUACAAAAAUUAGCCGGGCAUGGUGGUGGGUACCUGUAGUCCCAGCUACUCCGGAGGCUGAGGCAGGAGAAUGGCGUGAACCCGGGAGGCGGAUCUUGCAGUGAGCGGAGAUUGCACCACUGCACUCCAGCCUGGGUGACAGAGCAAGACUCCCUCUCAAAAGAAAAAGAAAAAAGAUGUAAAAACCAUUCUUAGUUUGUGGGCCUUACAAAUCAGGCCACUGGCCCAUUGCUUGUAGUUAGUUGAUCCAUGUCAUGCACCCUAAAAAUGGCUCUGUCACUGUGAGUGGCUUCAGUAGGAUUUUGAGAAUAAGUUUAUAUUCUUGCUAGGUAAAACAAAACAAAAACGACAGUAAUACCAAGGAAUCUCCCCCCCCUUUUACCCUCCAUUUGUGUUUAUUGCAUAUCCACUAUAACAACAUUAAAGGACCUUUAAAAGGAA